AUGACGGCUGUCUCCUCAAACAGGAACCCCGGGGACGACAGCUGUCUCCUCAAACAGGGACCCCUGGGACGAUGGCUCUCUCCUCAAACAGGAACCCCGGGGACGACAGCUGUCUCCUCAAACAGGGACCCCAAGAAUGACGGCUGUCUUCUCAAACAGGGACCCUGGGGACGACGGCUGUCUCCUCAAACAGGACCCCGAGGAUCACGGCUGUCUCCUUAUACAGGGACCCCAAGAAUGACGGCUGUCUUCUCCAACAGGGACCCCAGGGACGACGGCUGUCUCCUCAAACAGGGACCCCGAGUACGACGGCUGUCUUCUCAAACAGGAAUCCCGAUGACGACGGCUGUCUUCUCAAACAGGAAUCCCGAGGAGGACGGCUGUCUCCUCAAACAAGGACCCCGAGGACGACGGCUGUCUCCUCAAACAGGAACCCCGGGGACGACGGCUGUCUUCUCAAACAGGAAUCCCGGGGACGACGGCUGUCUCCUCAAACAGGGACCCCGAGUACGACGGCUGUCUUCUCAAACAGGAAUCCCGAUGACGACGGCUGUCUCCUCAAACAGGAACCCCGCGGACGACGGCUGUCUCCUCAAACAGGGACCACGAGGACGACGGCUGUUUCGUCAAACAGGGACCCCGAGGACGAUGGCUGUCUCCUCAAACAGGGACCCCGAGGACGACGGCUGUUUCGUCAGACAGGAACCCCGAGGACGAUGGCUGAAUCCCGAGGACGACGGCUGUCUUCUCAAACAGGAAUCCGGAGGACGACGGCUGUCUCCUCAAACAGGGACCCUGAGGACGACGGCUGUCUCCUCAAACAGGGACCCCGAGGACGACGGCUGUCUCCUCAAACAGGGACCCCGGGGACGACGGCUGUCUCCUCAAACAGGAACCCCGAGGAUGACGGCUGUCUCCUCAAACAGGAAUCCCGAGGACGUCGGCUGUCUGCUCAAACAGGGACCCCGGGGACGACGGCUGUCUCCUCAAACAGGAACCCCGGGGACGACGGCUGUCUCCUCAAACAGGAACCCCGAGGAUGACGGCUGUCUCCUCAAACAGGAAUCCCGAGGACGUCGGCUGUCUCCUCAAACAGGGACCCCGGGGACGACGGCUGUCUCCUCAAACAGGGACCCGAGGACGACGGCUGUCUCCUCAAACAGGGACCCCGGGGACGACGGCUGUCUCCUCAAACAGGGACCCCGGGGACGACGGCUGUCUCCUCAAACAGGAACCCCGGGGACGACGGCUGUCUUCUCAAACAGGGACCCCGAGGAUGACGGCUGUCUCCUCAAACAGGGACCCGAGGACGAUGGCUGUCUCCUCAAACAGGGACCACGAGGACGACGGCUGUCUCCUCAAACAGGGUCCCCGGGGACGACGGCUGUCUUCUCUAACAGGAGCCCCGGGGACGACGGCUGUCUCCUCAAACAGGGACCCGAGGACGACGGCUGUCUCCUCAAACAGGGACCCGAGGACGACGGCUCUGACAUGUCCACCAUCAAGUCUUCUCACUGUGGGGACAGCUUCCCCAACAUCCAUGCUGCCGGGUCUUCCGCCAGCCAUGCCGCCUCCUGA